GCACUGGGUUCGCCGCGCCGAACUGCAGCCAUGGAGCAGGCACCUCCGGACCCCGAGCGGCAGCUCCAGCCGGCGCCCUUGGAGCCGCUGGGCUCCCCAGACGCUGGGCUGGGGGCUGCGGUCGGCAAGGAAGCGGAGGGGGCCGGAGAAGAGAGCUCUGGGGUCGACACGAUGACACACAAUAAUUUUUGGUUGAAGAAGAUAGAAAUCAGUGUUUCAGAAGCAGAAAAACGAACUGGAAGAAAUGCCAUGAACAUGCAAGAAACAUAUACUGCUUACCUCAUUGAAACAAGGUCAGUUGAACAUACCGAUGGUCAGAGUGUCCUAACAGACUCACUAUGGCGGCGAUAUAGUGAAUUUGAGUUGUUGAGAAGCUACCUUUUAGUUUACUAUCCACAUAUUGUUGUGCCACCUCUGCCAGAAAAACGGGCAGAAUUUGUUUGGCAUAAACUCUCUGCUGACAACAUGGAUCCAGAUUUUGUGGAGAGGCGACGGAUUGGUUUAGAAAACUUUCUCUUGAGGAUUGCUUCACAUCCCAUCCUUUGUAGAGACAAAAUCUUCUAUCUGUUUUUAACACAGGAAGGUAACUGGAAGGAGACUGUGAAUGAAACUGGGUUUCAGCUGAAGGCAGACUCCAGGUUAAAAGCGCUUAAUGCAACAUUCAGAGUGAAAAACCCAGACAAGAGAUUUACUGACCUUAAGCACUAUAGUGAUGAACUGCAGUCUGUCAUCUCACAUCUUCUUCGAGUCAGAGCUAGAGUAGCAGAUCGACUCUAUGGUGUAUAUAAAGUACAUGGGAAUUAUGGUCGAGUUUUCAGGCAUUCUUGGAGUCUUUUCUUUUUUUUAAUUUCAUGGAGCUACAAAAUACUAGAGCGACCCUUGUGGUUUUUCAGUUCGAGUUCUAGAUCCAAGAGUGAAUGGAGUGCCAUAGAAAAAGAAAUGGGUGAUGGACUGCAGAGUGCUGGUCAUCAUAUGGAUGUGUAUGCAUCUUCUAUUGAUGAUAUUUUGGAAGAUGAAGAACAUUAUGCAGAUCAGUUAAAAGAGUAUCUUUUUUAUGCAGAAGCAUUGCGGGCUGUGUGCAGGAAACAUGAACUUAUGCAGUAUGACUUGGAGAUGGCUGCUCAGGACUUAGCAUCCAAGAAGCAGCAGUGUGAGGAACUGGUAACUGGGACUGUGAGAACAUUCUCUUUGAAGGGAAUGACUACCAAGCUCUUUGGUCAAGAAACUCCAGAGCAGAGAGAAGCCAGAAUAAAGGUGCUAGAAGAACAAAUAAAUGAAGGAGAACAACAGCUAAAGUCUAAAAAUCUGGAAGGCAGAGAAUUUGUGAAAAACGCAUGGGCUGAUAUUGAACGCUUCAAAGAACAAAAGAACCGAGACUUAAAGGAGGCCCUCAUAAGCUAUGCAGUCAUGCAGAUCAGUAUGUGCAAAAAGGGAAUUCAAGUUUGGACCAAUGCUAAGGAAUGCUUUAGCAAGAUGUAAUCCUGUGAAUUGAAUUUCUCUUCAAUCAAAGUGCCCCAAAACAGAAGCACAAGUAAAUAAAAGAAAUUUAAGUCACUACCUAGUAUACAUAAACAUAUACAAUAAGUUAAAUAAAUUCAGCUUUCUUUAACUUAAUUGUGGUCGUGUUAAUGUAGCACAAAAAAUAUAUUUUAAUGAAGAUUAAAUAUUAUAAUUUGAGGUUUUGGGGACUGGUGCUGAUUCCAAAAAGUUAAUUUAAUAAUAUAUACCAACAGAUUGUUUGUCACGCUUCUGAACCAAUGACUGAAUGUCAAGAUGUUCGUUAAUUUCUAGAUGUUUGUUUCAAGACCAGCUGUUUCAGAUCUAUUAAUGUAGGGAAUUUUUCCCUAAGAUUGAAUUCCUAUAUUUACUUGGUAAGAUCCACUAAUCUGUUAUAGGGAGUUGUUUUCUCUUGCCUUAUAGUUGAGCUAUUUGGUUUGACAAAGCUCAGCAGAAACUUGAUGUGAAAAAUCUACGAUUUUCUUCUACAUUCAUUGAUGCCCCUUGUAAUGUUUGCAUACACUAGAAAAUGCCUUCAAUUUGUGUUUUACCAGAAUUUUGAUACUGGUCAGAAAUUUUAUACUGCCAACAAAGAAGACUCAACUUCUCAGAUCUAUAAUGGGAUACAUUGUCAUCCUCUAGCAACUCCUAUAUAGAAAGUUUUAACUGAAUAUGUUACAUAUAAGAAUUAAAUUCUUCUCAAAUAAUUCUUAACCUCAGUAAUGAGCCUAAAUUUACUCUGCUUGGCUCUCUACACAUGGCAUUUCAGGGUAUAAGAUGUAGCAUUUCAAUGUGUAAGAUAUAUGUACUAAACAUAUGUGUUGCUAUCUUCAUCAUUAACAUCCUUCUUUUCUAUUGCUUGGCUGUAAUUUUUGUAAAGAUAAAUUAUAUUGUUUUUUUGUAUGUGUGUUUGUAGUAUAUGUUCAGAAGGCAAGCAUCUUCAUUUUGCUAGCUUUGCAGAAUCUUAAAAUGUGUACUCGUUAUUUCUAAUGAUGUAAAAAAAAAUCCCUAGUCCUGUUUAGCAUUUGACUUUUUUAUAUGUUUUAAAUGUUGCUGGAUUUUUGUGCUGUUUGCCAAACUUAUACAAUAAAUAAAUGAAAUAUUGUGCUGA